GGCGCGCGCCCCGCACGCGCGCCCCGCACGCGCAUAACGGCUUGGCUUACCUGUAACGGGUACACUUCGCUUCGCGUUCCUCGCUUGGCCUUGCGUUCCUAGCUUGGCUUGGCUGUUAGUAGCUUUGCCUGGUGUUUCUUGCUUGGAUUGGCGUUUCCUCCCUCGCAUUCCUUUGCUGGACUUGACCUUUUCUCUGCUGGGUUUGGCAUUCCCUUGACUGGGCUGGGUGUUUCCUUGGGAGGGGGGGCUUGGCCUUUCCUGGGGUGGGCGUGGGGUCCCCCUGGUGGGCGUGGGCUUUCCCCGGGUGGGUGUGGGUUUUCCCUGGGUGGGGUGGGCUGGGCUCCCUUGCUGGGCUUGGCAAGUUUUGGCUGGGAUUGACCUUUCUCUUCAAACAGAUUGGAAACCCAGGGUUUCCUGCUAGUUGGUGAAACUGGUUGGUAGACGCGAUCUGUUCGCUACUACCGGCCUCCCCUGGCUGUUAAAAGCAGAUGGUGGCUGAGGUUUGUUCAAUGCCCGCUGCCUCUGCUGUGAAGAAGCCAUUUGAUCUCAGGAGCAAGAUGGGCAAGUGGUGCCACCACCGCUUCCCCUGCUGCAGGGGGAGCGGCAAGAGCAACAUGGGCACUUCUGGAGACCACGACGACUCCUUUAUGAAGACGCUCAGGAGCAAGAUGGGCAAGUGUUGCCACCACUGCUUCCCCUGCUGCAGGGGGAGCGGCACGAGCAAUGUGGGCACUUCUGGAGACCAUGACAACUCCUUUAUGAAGACACUCAGGAGCAAGAUGGGCAAGUGGUGCUGUCACUGCUUCCCCUGCUGCAGGGGGAGCGGCAAGAGCAACGUGGGCACUUGGGGAGACUACGACGACAGCGCCUUCAUGGAGCCGAGGUACCACGUCCGUCGAGAAGAUCUGGACAAGCUCCACAGAGCUGCCUGGUGGGGUAAAGUCCCCAGAAAGGAUCUCAUCGUCAUGCUCAGGGACACUGACAUGAACAAGAGGGACAAGCAAAAGAGGACUGCUCUACAUUUGGCCUCUGCCAAUGGAAAUUCAGAAGUAGUACAACUCCUGCUGGACAGACGAUGUCAACUUAACGUCCUUGACAACAAAAAAAGGACAGCUCUGAUAAAGGCCGUACAAUGCCAGGAAGAUGAAUGUGUGUUAAUGUUGCUGGAACAUGGCGCUGAUGGAAAUAUUCAAGAUGAGUAUGGAAAUACCGCUCUACACUAUGCUAUCUACAAUGAAGAUAAAUUAAUGGCCAAAGCACUGCUCUUAUAUGGUGCUGAUAUUGAAUCAAAAAACAAGUGUGGCCUCACACCACUUUUGCUUGGCGUACAUGAACAAAAACAGCAAGUGGUGAAAUUUUUAAUCAAGAAAAAAGCUAAUUUAAAUGCACUUGAUAGAUAUGGAAGAACUGCCCUCAUACUUGCUGUAUGUUGUGGAUCAGCAAGUAUAGUCAAUCUUCUACUUGAGCAAAAUGUUGAUGUAUCUUCUCAAGAUCUAUCUGGACAGACGGCCAGAGAGUAUGCUGUUUCUAGUCAUCAUCAUGUAAUUUGUGAAUUACUUUCUGACUAUAAAGAAAAACAGAUGCUAAAAAUCUCUUCUGAAAACAGCAAUCCAGAACAAGACUUAAAGCUGACAUCAGAGGAAGAGUCACAAAGGCUUAAAGUCAGUGAAAAUAGCCAGCCAGAGAAAAUGUCUCAAGAACCAGAAAUAAAUAAGGACUGUGAUAGAGAGGUUGAAGAAGAAAUAAAGAAGCAUGGAAGUAAUCCUGUGGGAUUACCAGAAAACCUGACUAAUGGUGCCAGUGCUGGCAAUGGUGAUGAUGGAUUAAUUCCACAAAGGAAGAGCAGAAAACCUGAAAAUCAGCAAUUUCCUGACACUGAGAAUGAAGAGUAUCACAGUGACGAACAAAAUGAUACCCAGAAACAACUUUCUGAAGAACAGAACACUGGAAUAUCACAAGAUGAGAUUCUGACUAAUAAACAAAAGCAGAUAGAAGUGGCUGAAAAGGAAAUGAAUUCUAAGCUUUCUCUUAGUCAUAAGAAAGAAGAAGAUCUCUUGCGUGAAAACAGCAUGUUGCGGGAAGAAAUUGCCAUGCUAAGACUGGAACUAGAUGAAACAAAACAUCAGAACCAGCUAAGGGAAAAUAAAAUUUUGGAGGAAAUUGAAAGUGUAAAAGAAAAACUUCUAAAGGCUAUACAACUGAAUGAAGAAGCAUUAACGAAAACCAGUAUUUAAGUACAGUGGACAGCUUAGGAUUUUGACAACUGAGAAUGCUCAGUUCUGAACUGGAGAAUGUAAGACACAGCUAGGAAACACUGGAAAUGGAAAUUCAAUCAUGUCAUUGUAGACUGACUACUGCUCUACAUGAUUGUGAUCAAAGUCAGAUAGCUGAAAGGGACUUCUUUCCAGAGAACAAACAUCAACAGGUUUAUUUACAGGAGAAAAUGAAUUCUUAUAUAUCUCACCUAAAAGAUAACAGUGAGAUUCUUUCUGAACAACUCUAACGCUGACAGUAAAAUUAACAACCUAAAAAUUAAGCUCCAUCACACAGGAUAAAUUCUGAGAGAAAAGAUGAGGCAGGCCACCAUCUUUCCUGUUUGGGCAACUUAGUCAUUCCAGCGUGCGGGCUUUGGAGAGUACAAACUCACCAGGGACAGAAGAGAUCCUGUGGCAUAGCACAGCUGCUUUACCAAAUCAUGGCCAGAAUGCUUCUGUAAGCAGGCCCCUGAUCCUGUUCCUCGUCACUGGACAGGAUCUCCCACCUGAGGCCUCCAGCUACACCCACCAGUGUUCCCUGGCCAAUGGAGAUUUGAAACCUUCCUGGGACAGAGUUCCCAGAGAGAGGGGUGGGCCAUGAUGGGCAGGUCUUCCUGGCCUGGGUCUCCAGCCAGCCCCCCACUUGAGCCUUCAAGCCAGUAGCAACUCAGCAACUCCCUGGACAGAGCUUCCAGGAGCAACAGAAAUCCUCUCUGCCACUGCCUCUGCAGUGGAACUGCCCUUGCUACCCUCAGAAUGUCAAGGGAGCAAAGACCCUAAGUGCCAUAUUGACACCUCCAACAAGCUGCAGUUGACACAAGGAACAAGUCAGUCCAUCUUCCACGGGUACAACACACCCCUUACUGCUCAUCAACAGACAAGGAACCCUGGCUUGGGCCCACAGCACAGACCCUCCAUCCUGGGGUGAUUACAUUAAGUAACUCCUAACUUACACCUCUCUGGGGUGUAGCCCCCAGGAGACAAGGAAAGUGGUGGAGCAGCAAGUCAGCUGAUGUGGAGCCUGGAGGGCAGGGACAUCUAUGUCUCUAGGCUCCACUUGCUCUUAUGAGACACUUUAUCCCAGCACUUAAGGAGUGCUGAGGUCAGACCAGCCCCAUCUCACGUGCAAGAUUGCCCAGCACAGAUCAGGUCUAAGAGUUCUCUUCCUAAAAAGGGGGACUUGCUUAAAAAAGAAGUCUGGCCGCGUUUGUGUAGAGCAGUUGUGCUGUGCUGAGGAUUCACUUUUGAGAGAGUUCUCCUCUGAGACCUGAUCUCUGCUGGGCAGUCUUGCACAUGAGAUGGGGCUGGUCUGACCUCAGCACCCCUUAGUCUGCUUGCCUCUCCCAGGACCCCAGCCAGGCCACACCUGCUUAGAGGGCACUUUUGGGUGCCCACACCAUAGCUUCUGUACAAGCAGACCGUGGCUGAUCAGUGGAGAGCUGCAGCAAGGUGACCUCUACAGCCACGUACCAGCCUGCACAUUACCUCUCCAUACUGCAGCCCUUUAUAUGGAAACUUCCUACAUCACUUAGCUGUGUGUGUUUACACAGGUGGGUUUUGUUGUACUUGCCCUAACAGCAUAUGGGAAUGCAGCACACACCCCAACCCACACCAACUGCCACUGAAGAUGAAGCCAUGGUGGGCACAGAACCAAAAACCCCACCCCUGCUAGCAUCUCACCCUUGAGGUAAUGCUGUGCAGAGGAAAAGGGACCUUCUUAUACCCUGAGUGACCACUGUUGCUUGGGGGGGAUCAGAGAAGGCACCUUCACUGGCCAGCCACCCACCCCAAACCAGAACUACCUCCAGUGCAACAGCACACACAGUCAGCAGGGGCCCCCUGGCCCACACCCCAGCUGUUUUGCCUCCACCACUAGGUGAAUGCCCACAGGGAGGCAGGGACUUUUGCAUCUGCUAGCAUUCUGCCACAGCUGCCACACUUUGGUCCCCUCAGUGCGGUGGACUCCAAACCUCGAUGAGCCAGAGAACAAAGUUGUGGCCCAAUACAAGUUCCCCAGAGUUAAAGCACACAGUCCAAGAAUUGGGAGCUGCAUGUUGGCCCCUUAAAAUCCUCCAAAGACAAAACCUGUUGGCUGAAUCCACCUUACACCACAAUCAAAUCCUCAAGGUCAUCAGAUAUAAUAAAGGAAAAAUACCCUGUCCAAAGGUCAGCAGCCUCAAAGAUUGAAGGUGGAUAAGCCCAUAAAGAUGAGAAAAAGACUCUGUGCAAGAACACUGAAAACUCAAAAAUUCAGCAUGCUUUCUUUUCUCCAAAUGACUGCAUCAACUCUCCAGCAAGUGUUCAGAACUGGGCUGAGGCUGAGAUGUCUGAAAUGAUACAAGCAGAGUUCAGGAUAUGGGUAGGAACAAAGUUCCCUGAGUGAAAGAAGUAUGUUGUAAUCCAAUACAAGGAAGCUAAAAAUCAUUGUAAAACAUUGCAGGAACUAACAGACAAAAUAGCAAGUAUAAAGAAGAAAAUAACUGACCUGACAGAGCUGUAAAUCACACUAGAAGAAUUUUCAUAAUGCAGUCACACGGUGAUUGUGUGUGAUUGCAUUAUGAAAAUUAUUGUAGUAUGUGUGGGCACCUGAGAGUGCCCUGUAAGCAGAUGUGGCCAGGCUGGGGUCCUGGGAGAGGCAAGCAGACUAGGGAGGGCUGAGGUCAGACCAGCUCCAUCUCAUGUGCAAGACCAUCCAACAGAAUAGACCAAGAAGAGGAAAGAAUCCCAGAAUCUGGAAACUGGCUUUCUGAAAUAAAACAGGCAAACAAGAAUGGGGGAAAAAAGAAUGAAAGGGAAUGAACAAAACAUCCGAGAAAUAUGGGAUUAUAUAAACGACUAAAUCUAUGACUGAUUAAUGUACCUGAAAGAGAUGAGGAGAAUGGAACCAACUUGGAAAACACAUUUCAGAAUAUCAUUCAUGAGAAUGUCCCCAACCUAGCCAGACAGGCCAACACUCAACUUCAGGAAAUCCAGAGAACCUCAGUAAGAUAUGCCAUGAGAAGAUCAUCCCCAAGACACAUAAUCAUCAGAUUCUCUGCGGUCAAAAUGAAAGAAAAAGUGUUAAAGGCAGCUAGGGAGAAAGGCAACAUCACCUGCAAAGGGAAUUCCAUCAGACUUAGCAGACCUCUCAACUGAAACUGUACAAGCCAGAAAAGAUAUUCAACAUCUUAAAGAAAAGAAAUUUCAACCCGGAAUUUCAUGUCCAGCAAAAUUAAGCAUCAUAAGUGAAGGAGAAACAAGAUCCUUUUCAGGCAAGCAAAUGCUGAGGGAAUUCAUUAUCACCAGACCUACCUUACAAGAGCUCCUGAAGGAAGCACUAAAUAUGGAAAGAAAAGACCACCACCAGCCACUACAAAAACACACUGAAGUACACAGACAAGUGAUGCUAAAAACCAACCACAUACAUAAGUCUGCAAAAAAGCCAGCUGACAGCAUGACGAGAGGAUCAAAUCCACACAUACCAUUACUAACCUUAAAUGGAAAUGGGCUAAAUGCUCCAAUUGAAAGACACAGGGGGCAAGCUGGAUAAAGAACCAAGACCCAUUGGAGUAUGCCGUCUUC